AGUCUGUGGCCUGACUCCUUAAGCCAAGAGAAGGGUUGCAAGGCCGUGAAGGGCUGAGUGCAGGGCUCUGUGCAUUGUAGGUGCUCAGUGGUUUGCUGAAUGAGUGAAGGUUGUCUCCAUGGUGCGGGUGGCAGCUCAUCCCUUCUCAAACUUUUUGAGGAAGCUCCCCAAGCCUGCCCUAGUGGAUUAGAGCACUAAGAUCCCCCAGAGCUUUGGCUGCCAGGUGAAUGCCAGUUGCCCCCUACCCACACUCAGUCACACUUCAGACUUUCCAAACUCUUCCUCCUGGCCUAUGAAGUAAGCCCCAGGUGAACAGCCUCCACUGCCAUCACGACUUCCUCUCCUAGUAUGUCACCCACCAUGCUGCAGACGCAUGGUGGUCUUCCUGUUCCUGCAGCAUUACUCCCAAUUCAGUCUUACCUCAGCGCCUUUGCAUAUGCUGCCUGUCUGCCCAGGUCUUCGCAUGGCUGGCUUUACAACAGUCAAUCUCCUCUCAGAGGUCUUCCCUGGCCACCCUAUCUAGAGAGCCACUUCCAAUCUAGAGAGCCACUUCCAAUCACCACAUCUUCUUUUAUUUUUAUAGCCUUUAUCACUACCUAAAUUUUCAUGCGUGCUUAUCUGUUUAAGCAAUUGUCUCCCCAGUAAGAAUAUCAGUCCCUUUGCCGGCCGCGUGCCAUGGCUUUCGCCUGUAAUCCCAGCACUUUGGGAGGCCAAAGUGGGAGGAUCACUUGAGGUCAGGAGUUCGAGACCAGCCUGGCUGACAUGGUAAAACCCCUGUCUCUACUAAAAAUAAAAAAAUUUAGCCAGGUGUGGUGGUGUGUGCCUGUAAUCCCAGCUACUUGGGAGGCUGAGGCAGGAUAGUCGCUUGAACCCAGGAGGAGGAGGUUACAGUGAGCCAAGGUUGUGCUACUGCACUCCAGCGUGGGUAACAGAGCGAGACUCCAUCUCAAAACAAAACAAAAAGAACAAACAGAAAAAGAAUAUGAGUCCCUUGGAAACAGGAACCUUGUCUGUCUUUCUCAGUGCUGUGACAUCUAGCACAGUGCCUGGCACUGGUAAUAGGUACUUAGUAAGUAUCUGUUAAACGAAGGAAUCAUUAGUGGGACUGCCCCAUUCCUCUUGGAGGAAGCCCUGCUUUUAGCUUCAGUGUGAUUCCUCGAGCCUUCCUUGGGCCUCCUCUGUCCCUGUAACCACCUGUGCUAGGGACUGGGUGCUGGGGUUGUAGCUGUUCCCUGCCCUGGAGGUACCCACAGUCUGGCAAGGAGCUGGCUCCAAGGCUGAGUGGCAAGUGGGCAGAGCCAGUCUCAAUGGUCACCCUUACUGCUUCCCAGGGCUUAUUAGAAGCCCGAGAGCUGGGGUUCCAGGCCUGACAUUUUUCUGGGAUGUGGCUGGGGGCUUCACUUCCUCUCUGGGGAUCUCACUCCUUCUAUCUGGAAAAUAGGGUCAGAAUUCUCAGAUUCUCAAGGAUGGAGGGUUUGAGUUAACCUGAGUGUGAGUGUUUGUGAACUUGUGACAUUCAUGUUAGUCCUUGUCAUUUGUCCUGUGUUACACAUUCAGCAGGCCCCCAACACUGUAGAGAGUGGCAGACCCUGCUCUAGGGCAUCCAGGAAGGCUUCACUGAGGAAGGGACUUGGGGUGUGGACCCUUCAUUUUAUUGAUUGAGCACCUUCUGUGUGUCAGCUGCAGUCCCUGCGUUUGAGGAAGUGAGACCAGGGGGAUGUACACAAGAUGACUGUGCAGAGUGAUCUGAGCAAUGACAGGAAAGACUGCCAAGAGGCACUGGAUCCAGCAUCCUCUCCGCCCUCCAGGACCUCUUCUCUGUCACCUGGCUCAAUAGGUCCAAGGUGGAAAAGCAGCUACAGGUCAUCUCAGUGCUCCAGUGGGUCCUGUCCUUCCUUGUACUGGGAGUGGCCUGCAGUGCCAUCCUCAUGUACAUAUUCUGCACUGAUUGCUGGCUCAUCGCUGUGCUCUACUUCACUUGGCUGGUGUUUGACUGGAACACACCCAAGAAAGGUGGCAGGAGGUCACAGUGGGUCCGAAACUGGGCUGUGUGGCGCUACUUUCGAGACUACUUUCCCAUCCAGCUGGUGAAGACACACAACCUGCUGACCACCAGGAACUAUAUCUUUGGAUACCACCCCCAUGGUAUCAUGGGCCUGGGUGCCUUCUGCAACUUCAGCACAGAGGCCACAGAAGUGAGCAAGAAGUUCCCAGGCAUACGGCCUUACCUGGCUACACUGGCAGGCAACUUCCGAAUGCCUGUGUUGAGGGAGUACCUGAUGUCUGGAGGUAUCUGCCCUGUCAGCCGGGACACCAUAGACUAUUUGCUUUCAAAGAAUGGGAGUGGCAAUGCUAUCAUCAUCGUGGUCGGGGGUGCGGCUGAGUCUCUGAGCUCCAUGCCUGGCAAGAAUGCAGUCACCCUGCGGAACCGCAAGGGCUUUGUGAAACUGGCCCUGCGUCAUGGAGCUGACCUGGUUCCCAUCUACUCCUUUGGAGAGAAUGAAGUGUACAAGCAGGUGAUCUUCGAGGAGGGCUCCUGGGGCCGAUGGGUCCAGAAGAAGUUCCAGAAAUACAUUGGUUUCGCCCCAUGCAUCUUCCAUGGUCGAGGCCUCUUCUCCUCCGACACCUGGGGGCUGGUGCCCUACUCCAAGCCCAUCACCACUGUUGUGGGAGAGCCCAUCACCAUCCCCAAGCUGGAGCACCCAACCCAGCAAGACAUCGACCUGUACCACACCAUGUACAUGGAGGCCCUGGUGAAGCUCUUCGACAAGCACAAGACCAAGUUCGGCCUCCCGGAGACUGAGGUCCUGGAGGUGAACUGAGCCAGCCUUCGGGGCCAAUUCCCUGGAGGAACCAGCUGCAAAUCACUUUUUUGCUCUGUAAAUUUGGAAGUGUCAUGGGUGUCUGUGGGUUAUUUAAAAGAAAUUAUAACAAUUUUGCUAAACCAUUACAAUGUUAGGUCUUUUUUAAGAAGGAAAAAGUCAGUAUUUCAAGUUCUUUCACUUCCAGCUUGCCCUGUUCUAGGUGGUGGCUAAAUCUGGGCCUAAUCUGGGUGGCUCAGCUAACCUCUCUUCUUCCCUUCCUGAAGUGACAAAGGAAACUCAGUCUUCUUGGGGAAGAAGGAUUGCCAUUAGUGACUUGGACCAGUUAGAUGAUUCACUUUUUGCCCCUAGGGAUGAGAGGCGAAAGCCACUUCUCAUACAAGCCCCUUUAUUGCCACUACCCCACGCUCGUCUAGUCCUGAAACUGCAGGACCAGUUUCUCUGCCAAGGGGAGGAGUUGGAGAGCACAGUUGCCCCGUUGUGUGAGGGCAGUAGUAGGCAUCUGGAAUGCUCCAGUUUGAUCUCCCUUCUGCCACCCCUACCUCACCCCUAGUCACUCAUAUCGGAGCCUGGACUGGCCUCCAGGAUGAGGAUGGGGGUGGCAAUGACACCCUGCAGGGGAAAGGACUGCCCCCCAUGCACCAUUGCAGGGAGGAUGCCGCCACCAUGAGCUAGGUGGAGUAACUGGUUUUUCUUGGGUGGCUGAUGACAUGGAUGCAGCACAGACUCAGCCUUGGCCUGGAGCACAUGCUUACUGGUGGCCUCAGUUUACCUUCCCCAGAUCCUAGAUUCUGGAUGUGAGGAAGAGAUCCCUCUUCAGAAGGGGCCUGGCCUUCUGAGCAGCAGAUUAGUUCCAAAGCAGGUGGCCCCCGAACCCAAGCCUCACUUUUCUGUGCCUUCCUGAGGGGGUUGGGCCGGGGAGGAAACCCAACCCUCUCCUGUGUGUUCUGUUAUCUCUUGAUGAGAUCAUUGCACCAUGUCAGACUUUUGUAUAUGCCUUGAAAAUAAAUGAAAGUGAGAAUCCUC